GCCGCGCUGCGCCCGCUCUCCCGGCCCCGGCUGCCCCGCUGAGGGCUCCCCUCUCCCAGGCACCGCAGCCGCGCCCCCGCGUCCCGCCUCCCGAGCGGCUCGCUUCGCCCGAUGCCCCGGCCCCGUCCCGCGCACUGAGCGCCUGGCAGCAGGGCGCCGAGUCCCGGGGCGCUGCGGGGCGCUGCGCCGAGAACGGCCGGGCCUGAGCCCUGGGCGGCCCCCAGAGCCGAUCAGAGCGCGGGGAGGCGGGGGCGAGGAGGAGGGGACCCGCCGCCGGGGGCUGGCUGCUUCGCUCCGAGCCGACUUUUCGCCAAUGGUCCAAAGGGACAUGUCCAAGUCGCCUCCCACAGCGGCGGCGGCGGUGGCGCAGGAGAUCCAGAUGGAACUGCUAGAGAACGUGGCUCCCGCGGGGGCGCUCGGAGCCGCCGCACAGGUAGCGAGAGCGCGGCGCCUUCUCCUUCCUUUGUGAGCCGCCGGGCAGGGCACCGACCUCGGGUUCUCCCGGCGCCUCCACUGCAGGGAUCUCUAGCCUCGCACCUCCUCCCCUCGUCGCCUGCCCACCCUCUGCUCCUCUCCUGGCGCCGGGGACCCUGCCCCUUUGCGCCUUUUCCUGGCUCUGCCUCGGCUUCCAUUUUUCUCUGCUUCCGAAAAGCCAGUGGGGAAGGGCGGGGGAGACCUGCCAGUCCUCCCAGACUUCUCCCGGGUUGCUCCAGCUGGCCCUCCUCGCCCCUUCCCGGGAGAGGCACAUGGAGAGACAUGAAUCAGGGGAGUGGACUGGACCUGCUGAAGAUCUCAUAUGGAAAAGGAGCCAGAAGGAAAAACAGAUUUAAAGGAUCUGAUGGAAGCACGUCAUCUGAUACUACCUCAAAUAGUUUUGUUCGCCAGGGUUCGGCAGACUCCUACACUAGCCGUCCAUCCGAUUCCGAUGUAUCUCUGGAGGAGGACCGGGAGGCAGUGCGCAGAGAAGCGGAGCGGCAGGCCCAGGCACAGUUGGAAAAAGCAAAGACAAAGCCCGUUGCAUUUGCGGUUCGGACAAAUGUCAGCUACAGUGCGGCCCAUGAAGAUGAUGUUCCAGUGCCUGGCAUGGCCAUCUCAUUCGAAGCAAAAGAUUUUCUGCAUGUUAAGGAAAAAUUUAACAAUGACUGGUGGAUAGGGCGAUUGGUAAAAGAAGGCUGUGAAAUCGGAUUCAUUCCAAGCCCAGUCAAACUAGAAAACAUGAGGCUGCAGCAUGAACAGAGAGCCAAGCAAGGGAAAUUCUACUCCAGUAAAUCAGGAGGAAAUUCAUCAUCCAGUUUGGGUGACAUAGUACCUAGUUCCAGAAAAUCAACACCUCCAUCAUCUGCUAUAGACAUAGAUGCUACUGGCUUAGAUGCAGAAGAAAAUGAUAUUCCAGCAAACCACCGCUCCCCUAAACCCAGUGCAAACAGUGUAACGUCACCCCACUCCAAAGAGAAAAGAAUGCCCUUCUUUAAGAAGACAGAGCACACUCCUCCGUAUGAUGUGGUACCUUCCAUGCGACCAGUGGUCCUAGUGGGCCCUUCUCUGAAGGGCUACGAGGUCACAGAUAUGAUGCAAAAAGCGCUGUUUGAUUUUUUAAAACACAGAUUUGAAGGGCGGAUAUCCAUCACAAGGGUCACCGCUGACAUCUCGCUUGCCAAACGCUCGGUAUUAAACAAUCCCAGUAAGCACGCAAUAAUAGAAAGAUCCAACACAAGGUCAAGCUUAGCGGAAGUUCAGAGUGAAAUCGAAAGGAUUUUUGAACUUGCAAGAACAUUGCAGUUGGUGGUCCUUGACGCGGAUACAAUUAAUCAUCCAGCUCAACUCAGUAAAACCUCCUUGGCCCCUAUUAUAGUAUAUGUAAAGAUUUCUUCUCCUAAGGUUUUACAAAGGUUAAUAAAAUCUCGAGGGAAAUCUCAAGCUAAACACCUCAACGUCCAGAUGGUAGCAGCUGAUAAACUGGCUCAGUGUCCUCCAGAGCUGUUCGAUGUGAUCUUGGAUGAGAACCAGCUUGAGGAUGCCUGUGAGCACCUUGCCGACUAUCUGGAGGCCUACUGGAAGGCCACCCAUCCUCCCAGCAGUAGCCUCCCCAACCCUCUCCUUAGCCGUACAUUAGCCACUUCAAGUCUGCCUCUUAGCCCCACCCUAGCCUCUAAUUCACAGGGUUCUCAAGGUGAUCAGAGGACUGAUCGCUCCGCUCCUAUCCGUUCUGCUUCCCAAGCUGAAGAAGAACCUAGUGUGGAACCAGUCAAGAAAUCCCAGCACCGCUCUUCCUCCUCAGCCCCACACCACAACCAUCGCAGUGGGACAAGUCGCGGCCUCUCCAGGCAAGAGACAUUUGACUCGGAAACCCAGGAGAGUCGAGACUCUGCCUACGUAGAGCCAAAGGAAGAUUAUUCCCAUGACCACGUGGACCACUAUGCCUCACACCGUGACCACAACCACAGAGACGAGACCCACGGGAGCAGUGACCACAGACACAGGGAGUCCCGGCACCGUUCCCGGGACGUGGAUCGAGAGCAGGACCACAACGAGUGCAACAAGCAGCGCAGCCGUCAUAAAUCCAAGGAUCGCUACUGUGAAAAGGAUGGAGAAGUGAUAUCAAAAAAACGGAAUGAGGCUGGGGAGUGGAACAGGGAUGUUUACAUCCGCCAAUGAGUUUUGCCCGUUUGUGUUUUUUUUUUUUUUUUUUUGAAGUCUUGUAUAACUAACAGCAUCCCCAAAACAAAGUCUUUGGGGUCUACACUGCAAUCAUAUGUGAUCUGUCUUGUAAUAUUUUGUAUUAUUGCUGUUGCUUGAAUAGCAAUAGCAUGGAUAGAGUAUUGAGAUACUUUUUCUUUUGUAAGUGCUACAUAAAUUGGCCUGGUAUGGCUGCAGUCCUCCGGUUGCAUACUGGACUCUUCAAAAACUGUUUUGGGUAGCUGCCACUUGAACAAAAUCUGUUGCCACCCAGGUGAUGUUAGUGUUUUAAGAAAUGUAGUUGAUGUAUCCAACAAGCCAGAAUCAGCACAGAUAAAAAGUGGAAUUUCUUGUUUCUCCAGAUUUUUAAUACGUUAAUACGCAGGCAUCUGAUUUGCAUAUUCAUUCAUGGACCACUGUUUCUUGCUUGUACCUCUGGCUGACUAAAUUUGGGGACAGAUUCAGUCUUGCCUUACACAAAGGGGAUCAUAAAGUUAGAAUCUAUUUUCUAUGUACUAGUACUGUGUACUGUAUAGACAGUUUGUAAAUGUUAUUUCUGCAAACAAACACCUUCUUAUUAUAUAUAUAAUAUAUAUAUAUAUCAGUUUGAUCACACUAUUUUAGAGUCUUAAUGCCAAGUCAGCAGAUUUGCUUUAUGAAUUACAGGGACUAGAAAUGCCCACAUUCAGGAAAUUUGUAAUAACAUUGUCUAGACACCUAUCCUCAUUCUAGUAGAAAGUGUGUACAUACUGUAAAUAUGUGUGAUUGCUUGACUUGAAAAGGUUUGAAUUCUGAAUGUUAUACCAUCCUUGUAAGUAAGUUUGUAAUUUCCACCAUAAAUUAUGGUAAAUAUAAAACUCCAGAGGUUGUUCUACUCCAUACAGUUCACACUGAUUGUGACACAUUCUUAGUAGCUAGUGUCUGUUCUAGUCACUGCACUGGAGUCUACGAGCCGGAACUCGCUAUAUGCACGUGUGUGUGUCCGUAUGUAAGAAAGUGUGCACCGAGUGACUGAAUGGUUGAGAUGAAUUGGAAUGCUGAAGACUAACGAAGAAACUAGAGACUGAUAUCGAGCAUUCUGCCCACCUCGCUCUGUAUUUAAUUAAUUGUGCUAUAUGUUGCUUUAACAACCCAUUGAGCAGUCAGGGAAUGUGAGUAAGCUUGCUGCCAAAGGUAACUAGGAAAGCAUUCAUCUGCUGCCUCCUUGUUUUUGCUCCUAGAGAGUGAAAAUACAGGCAAUUUUACUGUGAGUGUUUCACUGGAAAUGUACAAUCUUUGUGUGUUAGAGUAUUUGUUUUAGUAAGAAAUGUUUACACAGCUUGUGGAAUUAUUUCGUGGGAAAAUAAAUUUUUAUAACUUCUCCCACUUCAAUUUCUAACCUUGCCUAUUGUUCCUGUUGUUUGUUUACCUCCCAGUUACCUACCAUUCCUCCCCACCACCGACUCCAGCAGGUUCACUGUCUGUCAGAACCCAGAAGUGCUUCUUAUAACCAAAGUUUCUGUUCUUCAGAAGAAAUCAGGGCAAAAUGGGGUGACUUGAAGUGAAUAAAAUGUUAAGAAUAUUAUCCUACAUAAGACAUGUACACAGAAGGGGAACCUUGAAGACAUUAUCUCCAUGCCUCAAUUACACUGCUGUAAGAAGCUUACAAUGUCAUCAUGUUUAAGGCUAAGACCUUUUCCGUGUCUCAAGUGUAUAUUUUGUCCAGUUAUAACUGGAUGGUAAGACAGUAUUAAGAGUGCAAGUACCUGGCACUUGAAGUUUGUCCCAGGAAAAUGCCUGUGUAUAAUUACCUAACUUCAGAUCUGCACAUUAACUUAUUUAACAAAAUAAAUCAGCCGGGCGCAGUGGCUCAUGCCUGUAAUCCCAGCAAUUUGGGAGGCUGAGGAGGGUGGAUCACCUGAGGUCAGGAGUUCAAGACCAGCCUGGCCAACGUGGCGAAACCCCGUCUCUACUAAAAAGAUAAAAAAUUAGCCAGGUGUGGUGGUGCACACCUGUAAUCCCAGCUACUUGGGAGGCUGAGGCAGGAGAAUUGCUUGAACCCAGGAGGUGGAGCCUGCAGUAAGCCAAGAUCACACCACUGUACUCCAGCCUGGGUGACAGAGUGAGACUCCAUCUCCAAAAAAGAAAAAAAAACAAAAAACAAAAAAAACUAUCCAGCAAAAUUAUAAAAUCUACUUUGUUUUGCUUCCUUGAUUAUUCCAAGUUCUUACCAAAUAUUCUUAGCCUUUUAUAAGUAAAACUGUUUUACAUUUAACUCCUUAUUUCCCUUACCCCCAAGAAAACGCAAUAUUAAAAAUGAUUAAGCUGGGGUGGUAGAGUAUACCUGUAGACCCAGCUACUUGGGAGGCUGAGAUAGGAGGAUCCCUUGAGCCCAGGAGGUGGAGGCUGCAGUGAACCGUGACUGUACCAAUGCACUCCAGCCUGGUGACAACCUGGUGUUUAAAAAAAGAAAAUAAAAAUUAGUUACAUAUAUAAUGUUUUAUCAGCUUAUAUAUGAAAAAAUUUCCCUCAGUUCGUUAAUUAGCCCUACACUGUUUACAUAAAUUUAUUUACUGAGUAUAAAAUCAGUAGUCAUAAUAAACUUGACAAUUCUUACAUUGGUAGGAAACCAUAUUCUAAUUAAAAUUGAAUUUAUAAAAUAUUUCUGAUAAAACUUUUGUCAUGGUAAGAGAUUCACAAUUAUUAGUUCAAUCCUUUAUUAUUUCAUCCCAAUUAAUGAUUUUAGAAUAUUUAAAUUCUUGAAACAUAGCUAGUAUUUAUCUUACUUGCUGCUAUCAUUAAUCCCUUUCAAAAAGUAGUGGUGAGAGUUUCCAUCUUUUUUAUUUUGUAUCUAGAUUCUUAGCUUGCACUUUACUGUAGAACAUAUUAGUGCAAAUCAGAAUAUUCCUCAAAGAACUAGCUUGAAGGAUUUGACAUAAGAGCCGCUAUAUGUGAAAAACUGUAUAGUGGACAUAUGUGUAAACUGUGUAGUAAAUCUGUAAAUGAGGAAAUAAUCUCAAGGGCAAUGGGAUAUUUACUGACCUGCGGAAUGUAAAGUUACAGUCUUUUCACACAACAAAGGCUUAACCUUAACCUACUCAGUUGUAGAGCCAUUUUUGUAGUCAACCUAGAAAAUGCUGGAAAUGUAUUUAAUAGUUUUUUUUUUUUUUUUUUUUGGUCAUAUCCAUUUCAGUCUUUCCUAUGCUCUUUCUCUACUGCUCAUUUAAGUUACUGUUACAAAAAGGUGCUGCUAAAUGUAGGAUGUCUUAGUCAUGUUGUACUUUGGGACAAUGCCACAUUUUUAACAUGGUCUGCUAUGCAUUCCUGUUAAACAUUCACUGUCAGCUACACUGAACUGUCUAACAAACCUGGUUUAAAGUAAUUCAUAUAAAACAAAUAAAGAGCUGGCUUCUGCACUGUUUAUUAGUAGUAGUAUUAAUUGCCAUGUUAGAAAUGAUUCAUGUAGUUGAGACUAUAUUAAAUAUUCAACACUUCCCAGCUGCAGGGCAUCUUUCUUGGGGCAAUGCUAAAUACUUUAUGUUCCUUUAGUAAUCUUCCUAUUAUGUCUGAUUAAAAAAAAAGAUACCUCCACGUAGAUAAAAUAUUUUAUUCAACGUGAGCUCUAGCAGAAUAAUCUGGGUCAGUUAUGAGUUCUGGAUCAAGAGUUUAAUUUCUGCUGCGCUGUACUUUUAACUAUUUGUACUUUGCUUCAUUAUUUAAAACAUGACACAGGGUUUUAAAGUAAAUGUACUCACUGUUGAACUUAAGUACUUCUUCUGUUUCAUAGAAAUGUUAAUAUUAAAUGUUAAAAUAUAUAUUAAUUUUCCCUCACA